AUGAGUGGCCGCUCCCGCUCCUCCAGUGCCGAGUCCUUCGGGCUGUUCUCCUGCAUCAUCAACCGGGAGGAGCAGGAGCAGACCCACCGGACCAUAUUCAGGUUUGUGCCUCGACACGAAGACGAACCUGAGCUGGAAGUGGAUGACCCUCUGCUAGUGGAGCUCCAGGCUGAAGACUACUGGUACGAGGCCUACAACAUGCGCACUGGUGCCCGGGGCUUCUUUACUGCCUAUUACGCCAUCGAAGUCACCAAGGAGCCCGAGCACAUGGCAGCCCUGGCUAAAAACAGUGACUGGGUGGACCAGUUCCGGGUGAAGUUCCUGGGCUCAGUCCAGGUUCCCUAUCACAAGGGCGAUGUCGUCCUCUCUGCCGCUAUGCAAAAGAUUGCCACCACCCGCCGGCUAACCGUGCACUUUAACCCGCCCUCCAGCUGUGUCCUGGAGAUCAGCGUGCGGGGUGUGAAGAUAGGUGUCAAGGCCGAUGACUCCCAGGAGGCCAAGGGGAAUAAAUGUAGCCACUUUUUCCAGUUAAAAAACAUCUCUUUCCGCGGAUAUCAUCCAAAGAACAACAAGUACUUUGGGUUCAUCACCAAGCACCUCGCCGACCACCGGUUUGCCUGCCACGUCUUUGUGUCUGAAGACUCCACCAAAGCCCUGGCAGAGUCCGUGGGGAGAGCAUUCCAGCAGUUUCACAAGCAGUUUGUGGAGUACACCUGCCCCACAGAAGAUAUCUACCUGGAGUAG